GGGCACCUCCUCCCACUGCGGGCAAAGGGCAGGCAGUUCGUGCGCGGACACAAGCACUGGCGGACCGUGGCCAUGGCGGGCGCUGAGUGGAAGUCGCUGGAGGAAUGCUUGGAGAAGCACCUGCCGCUCCCCGACUUGCAGGAAGUGAAGCGCGUUCUCUAUGGCAAGGAACUCAGGAAGCUUGAUCUGCCCAGGGAAGCUUUCGAAGCUGCCUCCAGAGAAGACUUUGAACUGCAGGGAUAUGCCUUUGAAGCAGCGGAGGAGCAGCUGAGACGACCCCGCAUUGUGCACGUGGGGCUGGUUCAGAACAGAAUCCCCCUCCCCGCAAAUGCCCCUGUGGCAGAACAGGUCUCUGCCCUUCAUAGACGCAUAAAGGCUAUCGUAGAGGUGGCUGCAAUGUGUGGAGUCAACAUCAUCUGUUUCCAGGAAGCAUGGACUAUGCCCUUUGCCUUCUGUACGAGAGAGAAGCUUCCUUGGACAGAAUUUGCUGAGUCAGCAGAGGAUGGGCCCACCACCAGAUUCUGUCAGAAGCUGGCGAAGAACCAUGACAUGGUGGUGGUGUCUCCCAUCCUGGAACGAGACAGCGAGCAUGGGGAUGUUUUGUGGAAUACAGCCGUGGUGAUCUCCAAUUCCGGAGCAGUCCUGGGAAAGACCAGGAAAAACCACAUCCCCAGAGUGGGUGAUUUCAACGAGUCAACUUACUACAUGGAGGGAAACCUGGGCCACCCCGUGUUCCAGACGCAGUUCGGAAGGAUCGCGGUGAACAUUUGCUACGGGCGGCACCACCCCCUCAACUGGCUUAUGUACAGCAUCAACGGGGCUGAGAUCAUCUUCAACCCCUCGGCCACGAUAGGAGCACUCAGCGAGUCCCUGUGGCCCAUCGAGGCCAGAAACGCAGCCAUUGCCAAUCACUGCUUCACCUGCGCCAUCAAUCGAGUGGGCACCGAGCACUUCCCGAACGAGUUUACCUCGGGAGAUGGAAAGAAAGCUCACCAGGACUUUGGCUACUUUUAUGGCUCGAGCUAUGUGGCAGCCCCUGACAGCAGCCGGACUCCUGGGCUGUCCCGUAGCCGGGAUGGACUGCUAGUUGCUAAGCUCGACCUAAACCUCUGCCAGCAGGUGAAUGAUGUCUGGAACUUCAAGAUGACGGGCAGGUAUGAGAUGUACGCACGGGAGCUCGCCGAAGCUGUCAAGUCCAACUACAGCCCCACCAUCGUGAAAGAGUAGCCGGCUUCAGUGCCUGCCUUGGGGUGAGGAAGACACCUCUGCCCCAGUGGAUUAGCAAGUGUGGCAGGCUUAACAUGUCCAGGUUCUCCCCAAUAACAUUGUCCAGGUUGGUUUUAAAAUUCCCAGGCAGGGGGAGAGUGGCAUGGGGAGUGACUUCUUAAUGGGUAAGGGGCUGCUUACUUCUGGGGUAUUGGAAAUGUUUGGGGACUAGGUAGAGGUGAAUGUACUAAAUGCCACUGAAUUUGUAUACUUCAGAAUGUUUGUUAUGUAAAUUUUACCUCAACUAAAAAAAAAAAUGCCCAGGUACUGCUUGUGCAGGUGGAUUUGAGGUUAGGCAGAUGAUGCUGUCCAUCCCGUACACCAGUGGGAAGAGGGUGAGGGCUGAUCCAGAGACCCUGAGCCUACAGCAAGGCUGUGGUGGGUCGGAUGGUCUUUGGAUGUGUCAGCUUAGCUAGGCCACAGUCACCAGUAAUUCAAUCAGACACUAAUCUAGGUAUUUCUGUGAAGGUAUUUUGUAGAUGUGACAGAAGUCCAUUCCCAAUUGACUAAGUAAGUGAGAUUAUCUCAGAUAAUCUGGGUCAGCCUGACCUGAUUAGUCAGAAGGCCUAAAGAACAGAGCUAAGGGUUUCCCUGAGGAAGAAAUUCUGCCUGAGGACAGCAGCCCAGUGCUUGGCGAGAGUUCCUGACAGUCUGCCCUUCUGAUAGCCUGCCUCACAGAGUUUAGACAUGACUAGCCAGCUCCUACAAUCACUGAAGUCAAUUCCUUGCAAUAAAUCUCAAUAUAUCCCCUACUGGUUCUGCUUCUCUAGUUGAAUCUGACUGAUACAGAUUUUGGUGCCAAAAGUGGUUCUAGAAAAAUAGAAUCUUAAAGAUGAGUUUUCUGCAUUGGUUCUGGAUUUUUUUAGAAUUCUUCCCUAGUUUGAUUGAACUUAAAGGCAUCAAUGACUCUAUUUCCAUAGAGUCAGGGUAAAGAGGGUAGUUGGUAGUCCAUGGCAUGGUGCAGCAAUAGUUAUUUAUGUGCGAGACUAGCCAUCAGCCAUCAGUUUGUGCCCAGAGUUCCAGCCUGCCCUUUCUGAUGGCUUGUCCUGUGGAUAUCAGACUUGCCUGACCAGAUUCCAUCAUCAUAGAAGGUAAUUUGUUGCACUAAAUCCUUUUAUAUCUCUAUCCAUCACCUACUAAUUCUGCUAGUUCUGCUAAUGUGGUUGAGCUCCAUUUUACACAUCAGAUUACUCACUUCUCUACACCUUGGUUUUUACAUCUGUAAAAUGGGACUGGGCCAGGUGUGGUGGGGUGGCUUAUGCCUGUGAUCCCAGCACUUUGGGAAGCCAAGGCAGGUGGAUCACUUGAGGUCAGGAGUUCAAGACCAGCCUGGCCAACACGGCGAAACCCCGUCUCUACUAAAAAUACAAAAAUUAGCUGGGCAUGGUGGCGCAUGCCUAUAAUCCCAGCUACUCAGCAGGCUGAGGUAUGAGAAUUGCUUGAAUCUGGGAGGCAAAGGCUGCAGUGAGCUGAGAUCACGCCACUGUGCUCCAGCCUGGACAACAGAGUGAGAGCCUAUCUCCAAAAAAAAAAAGGGGUGGGGACCAUAUUCCUGCUUUAUGUCAAGACACUGGUAAGAGACAGACUAGAUGGGCCAGGGAGCCCCUUGGCAGUUAUCAGUGCAGCGCCUAUUUAGCCCUGUCCCUGAACAACACGGCAAGAGCCCAACCUGCCAAGUCUCAAAUAGCAGUUAACCAGAGUAUCGGGUUGGAGGUGGGGUUGAGAUUCUGUAAUUCCCCGCUUAUUGUUCCCAAUCAGAGAAGGCAGCCAGAGAAGGCAGCUUCAUCCCUUCACUGGCCCAGCAGCUGAACUAUAUGGAAACCUCCAUGUCAGGGCUAGGGUACUCCUGGACAGCCACCAAGGAUGAGAAACCCUGAUGGAGCUGCCUGGCCACAGCUCUGCGGUAACUUCCUUGAACUCUCUGUGCUGCAGGUUUUCACUUUACCUAAUGGCCCUUCUUGCACCUUUAAAAAAAAAAAAAAAAAAUUCCAGUCCUACAGACACAGUGAGCUUUUUUGCCUGUUCCUUUAGCUUUCAAAAUUUAGUGUCAGCCAAGGCGGGCAGAUCACAAGGUCAAGAGAUGGAAACCAUCCUGGCCAACAUGGUGAAACCCCAUCUCUACUAAAAAUACAAAAAUUAGCUGGGUAUGGUGGCGCACGCCUGUAGUCCCAGGUACUCAGCAGGCUGAGGGAGGAGAAUCACUUGAACCCGGGAGGCGGAGGUUGCAGUGAGCCGAGAUCACACCACUGCACUCCAGCUUGGCGACAGAGUGAGACUCCGUCUCAAAAAACAAAACAAAACAAAACACCUUAGUGUUUUUGGUUUCUAGAGGGUGUAAUCAACCUAAUACAGAAGCCAGCUUAGGUGACAAAUUGGUACAUUUGUGAAACAGGCAUGAAUAAAUGGACCACAACUCUUUGAUUAUCUGCAACUCUCAUUGCCUGGAAACAGAACAGUCAGGCCCAUCUUAGAGUAUGCAGGCCCUGUACAGCCAAGGUCAUUUCAAGGUUUAACUCAUCCCUGGAACAUGCAGAUGCUCAGUAAACAUUUGAAUGAA